GCGCGGCCCAGCCACCUCCGGAGUCGCCGCCUCUGCUCUCAGUGCCCCGGAUCGGAGGCCGUCCAUCGCCCCUCGGGCCGACGCCAUGAAGAUCAAAGAUGCCAAGAAACCCUCUUUCCCAUGGUUUGGCAUGGACAUUGGGGGAACUCUAGUAAAGCUCUCGUACUUUGAACCUAUUGAUAUCACAGCAGAGGAAGAGCAAGAAGAAGUUGAGAGUUUAAAAAGUAUUCGGAAAUAUUUGACUUCUAACGUGGCAUAUGGAUCCACCGGCAUUCGGGAUGUACACCUUGAACUGAAAGAUUUAACACUUUUUGGCCGAAGAGGGAACUUGCACUUUAUCAGGUUUCCAACCCAGGACCUGCCUACUUUUAUCCAAAUGGGAAGAGAUAAAAACUUCUCAACAUUGCAGACGGUGCUAUGUGCUACAGGAGGUGGUGCUUACAAGUUUGAAAAAGAUUUUCGCACAAUUGGAAACCUCCACCUGCACAAACUGGAUGAACUUGACUGCCUUGUAAAGGGCUUGCUGUAUAUAGACUCUGUCAGUUUCAAUGGACAAGCCGAGUGCUAUUAUUUUGCUAAUGCCUCAGAACCUGAGCGAUGCCAAAAGAUGCCUUUUAACCUGGAUGAUCCCUAUCCACUGCUUGUAGUGAACAUUGGCUCAGGAGUCAGUAUUUUAGCAGUCCAUUCCAAAGACAACUAUAAACGAGUGACUGGGACAAGCCUUGGAGGGGGUACCUUUCUGGGUUUAUGCAGUUUAUUGACUGGCUGUGAAAGUUUUGAAGAGGCUCUUGAAAUGGCAUCCAAAGGUGAUAGCACACAAGCUGACAAGCUGGUCCGUGAUAUUUAUGGAGGAGAUUAUGAAAGAUUUGGUUUGCCAGGUUGGGCUGUAGCAUCUAGUUUUGGGAAUAUGAUUUAUAAGGAGAAGCGAGAAUCUGUUAGUAAAGAAGAUCUGGCAAGAGCUACUUUAGUUACUAUCACCAAUAACAUUGGUUCUGUGGCACGAAUGUGUGCUGUUAAUGAGAAAAUAAACAGAGUUGUCUUUGUUGGAAACUUUUUACGUGUCAAUACCCUCUCAAUGAAACUUUUGGCAUAUGCACUGGAUUACUGGUCAAAAGGUCAACUAAAAGCAUUGUUUCUAGAACAUGAGGGUUACUUUGGAGCAGUUGGUGCACUUCUUGGGCUGCCAAAUUUCAGCUAAAGCAUCAGGUCUCUCUCUCUGCUAAUAAAUGUCAUCCAAGAGGAACUAAAACCAGAGGCAUUAUUACUGCAUUGUUUGUCACUGGGAACCAAAGGAUAAAAGAGUAGCAUAAGCUGCUGAAUGUUGCCAUAUUAAAGGAGAGAACUUGGUAACGUGAAGUAUUUCUCAUUGAAAUGCUUUCCCUUUUGUAUAUAGCCAGUGUUAAAUCCUUAAAUGCAAUACAGCCUCUGAUUAUUGAGCUUCCUCUUAAAAAGAUUUUUUUAUUUUAUGUAGCCAACAUUGCAGUACUGUAUGCUCAAACACAAAUCUUAAAGUAUCGGAACUGUUUAGCUUAUGAAAAUAAUCGACUCUGAAUAUUUGUUACAAGUCUGUUUUAUGUGUUUUGAUUACUAGUGAGCAGAAAAUAACAUACCCUGUAUUCAAAAUUACUGAAAUGGCAAUCAAAGAUGAUCAUUUUUAUGUGAUUUUAGAAAUGUUAAGGCAAUACUACUAAUUAUUGUAGGUUUUUUUAACGUAUCACCCAAAGCAUGUAUGUGAUCUUUCCCCAUUAGUAUCUUUUUCUCAAAUGCCAUAAUUAACUGAAAUACUAUUAUUAAAUUUUCAUGAGAAUUCUAAAAUGAAUCCUGGGAAAUGCACGUUUGGUGAUGUUGCACUUUCUGUAUUUUACAGGAAUUAGUCAAUACAUGUUGAAAUGUUUAACAUUUUAAGAUUGGAGGCUUAAUUACUGGGAGUCUGUCUAAUGAAGUCCUGGGACUAUUGUAAUGGAAUAUGAUUUGAGUUCACUGUGCUCUUUUUGUUUGUUUGUUUUGGUCAUAUAUACAUUCAGAACUUUUAUUUUAAAACAACCACAAUAACAUUAAUAAUAGAAAAUUCAUCUGUAAAUAUUCACAGUCUAGUCACUGAAAAAUGGGAAAACCUCUACCAUGCCUUAUUAUUACCCUUUGCUGUUUGAGGAGCCAGAAAUAGAGGUGCAGUUAGAGGACGGUCACUUUUUCCAACAAAACCCACUCCAUAGCCAUGUGGAUUUUUAUCCAAAGGCUCAACAACCAGAGGGAAUGGUGAGACCUGAUAACUAAAAUACUGUUAUUGGCAAGGGUUUGAAAUGUGUAAGAACCUAGGAGGGAAAGGAAGAUUGAGCAACAUAGGAAAAGGGGAAGAGAGGCUGAGUGUCACCAAGGUCCAAACUCCAUUUAUAAAAAUACUGCAAAACCAGGAGUUGAUGGUAGAAAUGCAUAUGAUCCAUGGCAGGAGUAAAUCUCUCCACCUCCUCUAACUCUCUGAAAACUCUAGAGUUGGAGCAAGUCUUCCAUUUGCUUCUUAUCCCCUUAAAAGAAUGCCUUCCACUUCCCAACAGCCCCCAUCAAGGGACCCCAAGAGGCCACCAUGCUCUUAUCUCGCACUUUCUUUCCUAUUCCCCUUGCCUGAAUCUGGAGUGGGGUUGAGCCCUCUGCCUUCAACCUUAAGAUUUAGGAAGUUCUUUCCCCAACUGUCUAACUUGGAAAGGUAGAUGAGUCUGAAUUUUGAAGUAACGAAUGCAAAUUCCACUCAGCAGAGGCAAUGUUAUUUAUGUACAUAGGGAUAGUGGAAUGAGUUUUAAUAGAUUCUGUCCAAAAGGGGUUUGUUCCUCUUAUUUCCUCUAUGUAGGAAGUUGUGUCUUAGGCAACUUUAUCAGUAUCAAUGGAAAAAUGAUAGGCACUACAAUGAAAUGGCAGGAUGCCAAUAUGAGAUAUUUCAGGAAUAAUAAGAAAUACAGUUUGUUUGUAUAAAAUAAACUAUCUCAAGAAAGUUUUCAACGACAGUGAUAGUGUUCAUUUGUAAGAGAGAGUUCUAGAACUUCGAUGUCCAGUGCAGUAGCCACUACCCAUAUGUAGCUGUUGAGCAUUUGAAAUAUGGUUAGUCCAAAUUGAGAUGUGCUCUAAAGGACAAUAAAAGGUUAAAUAUCUCCUAAUUUUUUGUAUUGAUUACAUGUUGAAAUGUUAACAUUGGAAAUAUUGGGUUAAAGAAAAAUACACAAUUAAAAUGAAUCUUGGCCAGGCGCAGUGGCUCACGCCUCUAAUCCCAGCACUUUGAGAGGCCAGGGUGGGCAGGUCACCUGAGGUCAGGAGUUCGAGACCAGCCUGGCCAGUGUGGCAAAACCCUGCCUACUAAAAAUACAAAAAUUAGCCAGGCAUGGUGGUGCGCACCUGUAGUCCCAGCUACUUGGGAGGCUGAGGCAGGAGAAUUGCUUGAACCCAGGAGGAGGAGGCUGCAGUGAGCUGAGAUUGUGCCACUGCACUCCAGCCUGGGCGACAGAGUGAGACUCUGUCUCAAAAAAAAGAAUCAUCUGUUUCCAAUUAUUUUUAAAUGUGCUUACUAGAAAAGAUAAAAUCACACAUGGUUUACAUUUUAUUUCUAUUAAGACAGCACCGUUAAGAACAUAGAGCUUUGAGGAAUUGUGGUAUUAGAACCAAAUCUAUUUACCACAGUGAGCUUACAGGGAGUUACUCGAGAUCUUAAUAAAAAAUUAUAAUCUUUGGCAGCCUUCAUUAUGAUUUUGUGUUCUUAUUAUUCCAGUACCUCUAGAUUACAUAUGGGAAAAGCUAAAGAGCCACAGUGGUGAGAUGGUUGCUCACUCUAGCAGGUAAUUUCAGUUUGAAAGGAUAAAAUAUAUGAAUCAUAGUUCACAUUAACCAAAGUACAGUGAUGAAAUAACUUAGACUCUGACCAUUCCAUUUUUUCUUAAAGAUUGCCCUAAAUCUAUAGAUGCUAAUACAGUAUUUGCCACAGGUAUAAAACUUGUAGUUACUGUCAUUCAAUUAAGAUUCUUAUCUGUACAGAUAUACAAAUCAGAAACUUUUAAAAUAAAUUGAACUAAUGGAAUUUUGGCUCCAAUAUUUAGUCACUACAAUGGAAAUAUUAAAGCAAGGAACAUGAAGUCAUUGUAGGGUUUUAAAAUGGCUACUGACUGACAUGAAUUCAGAGUUUCAAACAGUCUAAAUUCUAAAAACUUAACUUUACACGCUUUUCCUCCUAAAUAACCACUCUAAUAAUUCAUACAUUCAUAUCUUCAGGUAAAGAAAACUGAAUUUUAAACAAUUGAGGCUGGGUGCAGUGGCUCAUGCCUGUAAUCGAAUAUAAGGACUUGAGUAUAAAAUUUGAAAACUACAUGGGGAAAUGUCUUUAUCAUGCAUCUCUUGAUAGUCUACUGAAAACUAUUAAGUAAACCUGCGGUCUGUAAACAAAAAAACCCAUAGUGAUACUUACCUUGUGUAAUGUAAACAAUUUUUUAAGCUCUUUAAAGUACAUCUAGAUUUACUGGUAAUGUAUAGAAGUCAAUUUUAUCCCCAAGCAUUUCUACUUCCUAAACCAUUAGCAAGAGUCUCAAAACAACUUCACUAAACUAUUGGACCUCCAGUGUUAACUUGCCAACAUAAAAAUCUGAAAAACUUUGUAAUCACUAUCAAAAAUACAAAAGAGAGAAUAAAUUCCCAGGUAAAAGGCUUUACAAAUUUUGGAACUAUUAUGCUUUUGUUUACUAAACACUGAUCCUUUUAGUAAUUCUGCAGUAUUGCCUCAGACUCCCACAAAGUUUCAAAAUAGCUCAUCUAUUAGAUUCCUGUAACAUUUAUUUGGGAUAAACGUGGUUUUGUUGCCGUUGUUCAUAAUAGAAUAAAAUAUUUAGCUUUGAUGGUUCAGAUGUAAUACAAAGAAAUAACUAAGUUUGGGCCUGAGAUAAAUGUGGUAAAGCAAGAAUGCAGAGAUGCUGUAAUGAUGAGUGAGUUUUAUAGCAUUACUGAGGACCUGAAAACUUGCUGCCAAGGACACUUUGAAGGUUUUGUUGGCUGGAAGAAGUGUCUCUGGAAUCCCACUCCUAGCUCUUCUUGAAUAUUUGAAAAGAAUUAGAUAAGGGCCAUGGGGACCCAGGUCACCCCACCUCUUCUUUUCAGUUUGGCUACAACAUUGGAGUCAUCAGUGCUCCUGAGACAGUCAUACAGGACUUUCUCAGUUACACUUUGAAAGAGAGGUCAGAAGACUCUCCCUCUGAGGUUUUGCUCAUGUCCCCCUGGCCCUUGUCUGUGGCCAUCUUCCCCAAUGGUGAUAUGAUUGGCUCCUUUCUGUUGCACUCUUUGUCAACCACUUUGGCAGGUGCAGUUCAAUGCUUAUCAUAAUUUGUUGGCUAUUACUGGUUGCCUUAUGGGAUUCUGCAGACAAGCUGAGUUGGUUGAAAUGCUGAUCCUGGGCCACUAGAUUACUGGCUUGUAAUGCGGACUCUGCACAAGUUUUGUGCCCAUGUACAUUGGAGAGAUCUCGCCUACUCCCCUUUGGGGUACCUUUAGUGCUCUCAACCAGCUGGACGUCGUUGGUAUUCUGGAGAUCCAGAUCUUUGGUCUGGAGUUCAUCUUGGGGUCUGAAGAGCUAUGCCCAGUGAUACUGGGCUUUACCAUCCUUCCAGCUGUCCUAUAAAGUGUAGCCCUUCCAUUUUGCCCUGGAAGUCGUAAGUUUUUGCUCAUUAACAGAAAGGAAGAGUACUAAUGAGAUCCUUCAGCAAUUGUAGGGGACUCAGGAUGUGUCCCAGGACAUCUAGGAGAUAAGAGUGCUAGGAUGAUACAAGAAAAGCAAGUCACUACACUGGCGCUCUUUAGAGUACCCAGCUACCAACAACCCACUGUCAUUUCCAUCAUGCUCCAGCUCUCUCAGUAGCUCUCUGGAAUCAAUGUUGUCUUCUAUUACUCAAUGAGAAUCUUCAAGGAUGCAGGUGUUGAGAAGCCAAUCUAUAGAUUAGUGCAGGAGUGGUUAAUAUUAUCUUCUUGACUGUAGUCUCUCUGUUUGUGGUUGAAAGGGCAGGAAGGACUUUACAUAUGAUAGGUCUUGAGGCAUGGCGUUUUGUUCUGUCCUCAUGAUUGUUUCUUUGUUAUUAAAGGAUGAGUAUGGUGGGAUGAGCUUUGUCUGUAGUGGGGCUAUCUUGGUCUUUGUGGCCUUCUCUGAAGUUGGACCAGACUCCGUUCCCUGGAAUACUGUGGCCACACUCUUCAGUUUGCAAUAGCAGUGGCUGGUUGCUCCAACUGGACCUCCAACUUUCUAGUUGGAUUGCUCUUCCUGAACAAUUAUUAUCUAGUUUAAGUGUGUUGUUGCUUUAGGGUCAUGGCAUGCUUAUGUAUUUCUGUUACCAUCUGACCAUGGUACUAUGCCAAGUUCUCUUAGGGGACCUGAAUCUUUCCAGUAGACCACAUUUGAGAGAGUAUGAGUCAACUGGGCAUAGUUCCCAACAACCCAAAAUACAUACGUACUUCACUGAAGCAGAUCUCAUGAUUCCAUUGACUUCAUUUCUAAAAUUGGACUUUGAGCAGCCAAUUUCUAAGGAUUAAAAAGAAACUUUAAUGCAUUGUAGACCUCUGUACACAGAAAAAUCUUUGUAACUUUUGGGCUUAAUUUUCAUUCUUAAAAAAUCUGGUAACUUUUUCAAAUGCAACCACUGUCAGUUUGCUGUGAGGCUAGGCAAACAACACAAGGUAUAGAAUUUCCCAUCACCACCACCCUGACCCCGCGAGAAGAUUGCCUUUUAAUUAGAGACUUGUAGAACUAGUGCCUUUUAAGUUCUACACUCAUCUUUUCCAAAGACUAUUAGUAAACUUGCCAUGUAAUUUGACAUGGCAGUUCCUUGCUCAGCUACUCUAAAUAAAGUUGGAAAUUAGGUGGUCUCUUAGUUUGGGUAAAGUCAGUACUAUUGCCAGUAAUAUACAUGGUAAUUGAAAGCCCUUAAAGUGGUUCAGAUUAUUUGCCAAAUAUUAGACUCUAUAAAAAUUUCUGAGGUUUUUUUUCUUUUACCUUUGAGUGUACAUGUGAUUGCUAUAAUGUAAAUACCAGUCCCUUAAAGACUGUUUCUAUAAGCAGAAUGAUGCAGCACAAAGUGGAAAGGUUUUCCUCUUAUUCCAGCAGUAUUCUUGCCUUCAAAGAGUAGUCCAUCUUGCCUUGAUUUUUAAGGUUGUUUUCUUGGAUGGAAAGCUUAACUGGAUAGUAAUUUCCAUAUGUUCUUUAUAACCACUCUGUAUAUUAUAAGCAAAGUUUUUUCAUAUUGUAUCUUUUUCUGUUGAGCACUUUAUGCAUUUUAGUCUAUUGCAUUUGAGAAUGUAGUUUAGAAAUUCACUGUUUAAAGCCAUGUGAAAACUGAUAGAGGAUAAUGAAAAUGAGUGUACAUUAUUUUGAAUUUAACUUAACUGUUUUGUGGUGGGUGUGAACAAAACAUUAGAAAUAUAUUAUCUUUUUGUGAUAAUACUCUCUGACCUCACUUAAAGUGAUCUGCCAUGAGGUAUCCAUGAUCAAGUUUAUGUUUAUUCUAAUACCUAAGGAAUUCAGCCAACUUUGUUUCUAUCAUCAGAUAAUCUCAGAAAAUAGUGUGUUUUAUCUAUAUUACUGCCUCUUUUCAAUAUUUAAGAGAAUAAUUGUCUUCUGGUUUCUACUGAGCCUAGUAAUAAUCACUAAAGACCUAAAAAAGGAAUUCCUUCUGUUAAGAGUAUUUGGAUAGCCCAUUCACGAUAAUGGUGGUGUGAAAAUCAAUCAUCCCAGCUUUUCUGACAUAUCUAAAUUUUGAAUAAUUAAUUUCCACUUCCAAAAAAUUCAAAUGUUUUCUCAAAGCAGUCACUACUUAUUUGCAUUAUUCCUGCAUAUUCAGUGAAUGUGAGGUCAUAUUUGGUAUUGUAUUAGAAGUAGUGUUGGUCACUGGUCUUGCCUCUUUGAACAUUAUUUUUAUUUGUAAAAUGAGGGAGUUGGUUUGUUAUGAUGGGAAAUGAGUCAGUUUUCAGGGUCCUGAGAAAAUUGCUUCAUUCAUGGCUGUGUUUGAGAUAACUAAAGUAAAUUUUUUUUCAGGUAUUUGGUGUCAUGUUUUGGAGUUAAUAUUUAGUGCUUAUAUAAUUUUAAGUUAUUACAUAAUUUUUAUUGGUAUAUAUUUGAUAGGUACUAGGUAUUGGAUUCUCACCAAACCAGUAGAAUGGUAUUCUCUCUUAAUAUGUGAUUGCCUGUAAUGGCCAGGUAGAUAUACCUUAAAGUAAUAUGAAAGGUUUUAUAUGUAUAUUAAAAUGUUUGUACUUUUAAAUCUGUAAAGGUUAUCUGGAAUUUUUACUGUGUUAACUUCAGAAUUAUAUGGGCAUUAUGACUUUUUCAUUGUACAAAAAAUUAUUCAUAAAUGUUAGAAUACAGAUGUUCCUUGACUUACAAUAGGGUUAUGUUCCAGUAGACCCAUUGUAAAUUGAAAAUACCGUAAGUUGAAAAUACAUUUAAUACGCCUAACCUACUGAACAUCCCAGCUUAGCCUAGCCUAUCUUAAAUGUGUUCUGAACACUUAACGUUGGCCUUUAGCUGGGCAAAAUCAUCUAAUACAAAACCUAUUUUAUAAUGAAGUGUUUAAUAUCUCAAAUAAGAGUAUUGUACCACAUAUCGUUAUCCCAGGAUAAUAUCAGAGUACAAAAUUUGAAGUACAGUUUUUAACUGAAUGUGUAUUGCUUUUGCCCCAUUAUAAAGUUGAAAAACCAUAAGUCAAACCAUUGUUAAGUCGGACUGUUUGUGUUACAUAUAUUUGGGAUUUUUUAGUGGCCCUUUUUAAAAAGCUGUUUCUUAUUUCUGAUCAUUGUGAGUGGGGAUAGAUGUGGGAAGAACCAUGUCUCUACUAAAAAUACAAAAAAUAGCCAGGCUUGUUGGCACACACCUAUAGUCCCAGCUACUCGGGAGACCGAGGCAGGAGAAUCACUUGAACCGGGAGGCAGAGGGCAGAUCAUGCCACUGUAUUCCAGCCUGGGCAACAGAGUAAGACUCUGUCUCAAAAAUGAAUGAAUGAAUGAAUGAACGAAUGAAUGUACUAUGAGCUGAUACUGGGAUUUCAGGUACCGCAGUUUGUGCUGAAUGAUAUGUUUGGGGUAAAUCAGUUUUUUUCUUAUAGAAUUUCGGCGUUUUUGCUGCAACUGCCACUAAUUUUGCAUUUAAAAGAACAAAAGAGGAAUGUAUUUUUCAAAGGAGUGAAUGAGGUUAAAAUCAAGAUUUUGAAUGGUAUAAAUAUGCAACUAAUUCAGUUGUAGGAUAUUAUUAAAUUUUUUAUUGCUAAAUAUGUUUCUUUCAUACGUUGCAGUGCUUACAGUUCCAACAGCUUUCCAAGAAAACAUUUCCAUAUUUGUGUUAUUUGUAAAGUAUACAUAAAUAAUGUAAAAUAAUUUGGGAUUAUUUCAACUUUACAUUGUAUGUCUGAAUUUCAUCGAUGUUGUACCUGGCUCAGUCAAUAGUUGUCACAGGUAUUAAGCCAUUUUGGAAUUUGCCACUUUUUUCUGGGUAACCUGUUUUAGUUUAGUUUACAGCAUUUAGAAACAGAAGGUAACUUUAUAGAAGUAACACCAAUAUCCUAGUCUGCUUGCCCCGAAUAUAACUAAUAGUAUUAGGAUGUAAGCAAUAUUAAGAUGGUUUUUAUUAUUUUUUAUACACUGUGUGCUUUUACUUUUUAUUUAAACUACAGCAAAAAACUGAUUUUUUAACUAAAAUUGAAUGGCGUUUAUCUUAAUGACCAGUUAUUGACCAAAGUGUACUCAGAAGAUGUUAUUAUGUCCCAAUCUAAGGAAUCCUUUAAUUUGGGGAUUAAUUUUACUUACACAUGCCAUUUCAGUUUCAGUUGCCUCAUUCUAUUACAUCAUUCUUGUCAAGUCUAAGCUUUAUCAUGUCUGAAUUCUUUUAACACUGAAUCUGUGAUGUAAAAAUGUAUGAUGUGCCAUAAAUUUUAUUCAUAAUAAACUAAGUUAUAGCCUAUUGUAAUCUGUAAAACAUUUCUUGUAAAUUACCUAAUUUAUUUUUUCAUUUAUGUACAGUAUCUUAUGUAAAUUUGAAAAAUGUUUGCCAUGGCGCAUUCUGUAAACAUUCCCGUAUUCUUUUCCUUAAUGCUUAUUUGCAUGAAGGUAACUUGGGUUUUGCUUGUUUGUAUUGGAUAACCAUUAAGCCAACUUCAGUUUCUCUGCCUUUUUUUCUGUAGUUUAACCAUUUCUAAUUUUGUUCAUAUUCUAAAUAGAUGUUAGAAUCAUACUUUUUAUUUUCUACUUUCUAAAUAAAUUAUCUAAGUUGUUUACUA